CUCUUGGCAGGCUGGGACCUCAGGCGCACACAGGGCUCAGCUGCCCCUCCUUUGAGGCUGCUGCAGAAGGCAGGCCCUGAGACGGAGGAAUCAGCUGCUUUCACUUGCUCUGCUCCAAAGGAAAAGAAGGAAGGGAGGAAAAAAUCCCAGGAUCCGGACGUAAGCAGGGGUGGUGAUUGCAGAUCCCCACAUCACAGGCAUUGCCAGGCCCCUGCCUCCAAGACACUGGGCUGGCUACAGCCCCUGGCAUGGAGGCUUCCUAGCCCAGCUCCCAUCAUGAGUGAUGAAAGCAGCAGUCCCUCCAUGGGCUGGAAGCACUGGCCAGUCACUUCUGCCACCCAGGAUCUGUGGGGCAUGGACCCCCGAUGCAGGGAUGCCUUGGGAUGCUCCCCUCCAAGGGCUGUCCUGGUCCACGCUGCAGAUGGAGCGGAAAGGACUGUGCUGAGGAGAGGCGCCGAGACCUGCCAAAUACUCCCCAGGAGCUGUAAGGAGGCCACAGGUACCACAGCGCAGGCGACAAGGGCAUGGCUCUACAGGUACUGUCCAGCUGUGCACACCAGCAAGGGCUGCCCAGCCCCGCCUGCCACUCUGCCUCUCAAGGCAGAGACAUUUGUUUGGGUGAACAAUGCAUCUGCACAUUCCCAGAGUGUUGCCAAGGCCAAAUAUGAAUUUUUAUUUGGCAGAUCUGAAGGGAAAGCUCCAGAUACUAGUGAUCAUGGAGGAAGCACUUUACUCCCACCAAAUGUCACAAAUGAAUUUCCAGAAUAUGGGACCAUGGAGGAAGGUGGAGAAGGCCUAAGGGCUUCUCUGGAAUUUGAUGGUGAGGCUCUGCCAUGCCACCCACAAGAGCAGCAGGGUGUCCAGCCUCUUACUGGCUGCCACUCUGGGCUCGACAGUGUUACAGAAGGACCAAAAGAUGUCAGAGAGGCCCCCUCUCAAAGUCAUCUCAAGGAACAAAGUUUACAGCCCAUUGACUCUUUGAUUUCAGCUCUGAAAGCCACAGAAGCCAGAAUCAUUUCCGGAACAUUACAGGCUACAAAGGUACUGGACCAAGAUGCUGUUUCUAGUUUUUCAGUUCAGCAGGUGGAAAAAGAGCUGGACACUGCCAGUCGUAAAACACAGAGAGUCAACAAAACGCUCCCUGCUGGCCAAAAAAAUUUACCAGAAAUACCUCUUUCAGCUGAAGUAACAACGGAGGAAAGUUUUUAUUUGAGCAUCCAGAAAGAUCUCACCGCGCUGUUAACUGGAGACACUCAGGCAGAGAUUUCCCAGAUAAUGAAUAAUGGGAGGAAAGGGGCUGUCUGUGUGCAGGAGCCAUCUUGUCCUUUGGCCUCCCUCGGGAGCUCAGCAGUGACCUGCCACUCUGCAGGCAGUGUUGGUUUCUUGAAAGAGCAGAGGUCUGCUCUUGGGAGAGAGCACCCAGGGGGAUGUGAUCGAAGCAGCUCCAUGGGACGCCCAGGCCGGGUCAAACAUGUGGAAUUUCAAGGAGUGGAAAUACUGUGGACAGGAGGAGACAAGAGAGAGACCCAGCAUCCUAUAGAUUUUGAGACAUCACUGCAAAGAACAGCCUCUCCUGACAGCAAAGAGUCUUCCAAAGUGCCACGCCAUCUCAUCUCAUCAGCUGGUUUGUGUAAUUCAAGUAGUUUAACUGAGAAUGUUUGGGAUGAAUCCUGGAAAGCUCCUUCAGAGAGGCCUGGCACUAGCUCGGGGACAUUUUCCCCUGUGCGUCUUGAUGAGAGUGGAGAGGAUGAAGUCUUCCUACAGGAAAACAAACAGCAUCUUGAGAAGACACCUAAACCAGAGAGAGACAGGGAAAGGAUCAGCGAACAAGAGGAGCACGUUAAGGGGGAAGAUGAAGACAUCCUUGGGCCUGGAUAUACGGAGGACUCCACCGACGUGUACAGCUCCCAGUUUGAAACCAUUUUGGACAACACUUCUUUAUACUACAGUGCAGAGUCCCUGGAGACAUUAUACUCAGAGCCUGAUAGCUAUUUUAGCUUUGAAAUGCCCCUCACUCCAAUGAUACAACAGCGCAUUAAAGAAGGUGGUCAGUUCUUGGAGAGGACAUCAGGGGGAGGACAUCAGGAUAUCCUGAGUGUGUCUGCAGAUGGUGGCAUCGUGAUGGGCUAUUCUAGUGGCGUCACCAAUGGGCUGAAUGAUGCCAGCGACUCCAUCUACACGAAAGGCACCCCGGAGAUUGCUUUCUGGGGAAGCAAUGCUGGGGUGAAAACAACACGGCUAGAAGCUCAUUCUGAAAUGGGGAGCACUGAAAUUUUGGAAAAGGAGACCCCAGAAAAUCUCAGUAAUGGUACCAGCAGCAAUGUGGAAGCAGCCAAAAGGUUGGCCAAACGCCUUUAUCAGCUGGACAGAUUCAAAAGAUCAGAUGUUGCAAAACACCUUGGCAAGAACAACGAAUUUAGCAAACUAGUUGCAGAAGAAUAUCUGAAGUUUUUUGAUUUUACAGGAAUGACGCUGGAUCAGUCACUCAGGUAUUUCUUUAAAGCAUUCUCUCUUGUGGGAGAAACUCAAGAACGAGAGAGAGUUUUAAUACACUUCUCCAAUAGAUAUUUUUAUUGUAACCCAGAUACCAUUGCUUCACAAGAUGGAGUCCAUUGCCUUACCUGUGCAAUAAUGCUUCUUAAUACCGAUCUACAUGGCCACAAUAUUGGAAAGAAGAUGACCUGUCAGGAGUUCAUUGCAAAUCUGCAAGGGGUAAAUGAGGGUGUUGAUUUCUCCAAGGAUCUGCUGAAAGUGAAGCUUUCCCAAUUUUUUUCAUCUCUUGUUUUUGGGCACCAUUAUUUCCGUAUCUCAACAUGCUCUUCUGCCCUGGCGGCUCUGUACAACUCAAUCAAGAAUGAGAAGCUUGAAUGGGCAGUAGAUGAUGAAGAGAAAAAAAAGUCUCCCUCAGAAAGUACUGAGGAGAAAGCUAACGGAACACAUCCAAAGACCAUCAGUCGUAUUGGAAGUACUACUAACCCAUUUUUGGACAUUCCUCAUGAUCCAAAUGCUGCUGUGUACAAAAGUGGAUUCUUGGCUCGGAAAAUUCAUGCAGAUAUGGAUGGAAAGAAGACUCCAAGAGGAAAACGAGGAUGGAAAACCUUUUAUGCUGUACUGAAGGGAACAGUUCUUUACUUGCAAAAGGAUGAAUACAAGCCAGAAAAGGCCUUGUCUGAAGAGGACUUGAAAAACGCUGUGAGUGUGCACCACGCAUUGGCAUCCAAGGCCACGGACUAUGAGAAGAAACCAAACGUGUUUAAACUUAAAACUGCCGACUGGAGGGUCUUGCUUUUUCAAACUCAGAGCCCAGAGGAAAUGCAAGGGUGGAUAAACAAAAUCAAUUGUGUGGCAGCUGUAUUUUCUGCACCACCAUUUCCAGCAGCAAUCGGCUCUCAGAAGAAGUUUAGCCGCCCACUUCUGCCUGCCACUACAACAAAACUGUCUCAGGAGGAGCAACUGAAGUCACAUGAAAGUAAGCUGAAGCAGAUCACCACCGAGCUGGCCGAGCACCGCUCAUAUCCCCCCGACAAGAAGGUCAAAGCCAAGGACGUCGAUGAGUACAAACUGAAAGACCACUAUCUGGAGUUUGAGAAAACCCGCUAUGAAAUGUAUGUCAGCAUUCUCAAGGAAGGAGGCAAAGAGCUACUGAGUAACGAUGAAAGCGAGGCUGCAGGACUGAAGAAGUCGCACUCGAGUCCUUCGCUGAACCCGGAUACUUCUCCAAUCACUGCCAAAGUCAAGCGUAACGUGUCAGAGAGGAAGGAUCACCGACCUGAAACACCAAGCAUUAAGCAAAAAGUUACUUAGAGUCCAUCUGCGGCCAGGAAGUGCUGGUCAUGGAGCAAAAUAGGGUUUUUCAAGAUCUUUCUGGUAAUCCGUGAAUAUAUUUAAAAAAAAAAAGUCUGUGACAAAACGGUGCAUUAGUAAUUUUUUCUAUUGUAUAUUUUUGUUAGUUUCUGUACAGAUUGUCUUUGCUCUUGAUUUCUUUUGCUUUGAUGAUUUUUGCAACUUGAUAGCUAAUGCACCUUUUCUGUGAGGAGGAGGGGAUCGUGAUUUCAGAAUGAAUUAUGUAUCCCUUCUCUUUUGGUUUUCUCUUGUUUGCAGUCUGCUCAGUUGUUUUAUGUAUUCUCAUAUCAACUGUUAAACUUUUUUUUAAGGUUAAAGAAUUUAAUCCAUUGUGAAACACUUAACUGGACAAACUGUAGUUUUAGUAAAUUCUAGCUGGAGUUAAUAUACGCCUUUAUAUGUGAAAUCUUGCCCAGUCACAGAGGUAGAAUUGAGCACUCACAGAUGCUCCAGUAAGAAUCACAGUGCUGGGAAUCUAGUUGCUCCAAUAUGAGGCAGCUUCAUGUGCAGCUUAGCACUUGUUGUUGAGAUCGGACCCUGCUGGAAGCAGGGAAAAGAAGCGUGAAGAUCGUAGGAUUGAGAACUUAGGGAAGCACAUUAGCUUGCUUGAAGUGCUGAUUCCAUUUCAGCCAAGCAAGGGAAAGAGGAAGUGGAGUCAUUUUGCCUUUGAAGGCUGAGGAAAGAUUGAUACCCAGUUAAUUUUGUUUGCUAAAGGAUGGGGGCAAUAAUCGGCCCUUGAGGAGCUGCAGCAGUAGGCAUGUGCUCAGUCUGCAGGAAUUGUUACCUCACUCCCACAGGGUCUAGACUAGAAAUCCAUCAUCUCUAUCGUUGAUAUCCUUCCAUCCAGGAAUAGAUUUUUCUUACUCUACAUAUGUGUGUGUGCGUGCGUGUGUGUGCGUGUGUGGGCAUGGGGUUGUGUCCUGGUUGUGAUAUUGAGGUCUUCCUUCCUAACAAAUUAAUACUAAAAUGAAACAGCUUUUCUUGUGUCCUUAAGACAAAAUAAGGAAGGAAAACGUAGCUGCAGUUGUCCACGAUGGAUAUUGGUUCUUUAAAAUAUAUCUGAAAGUAGUAGUCAGAAUGAAUUAUGGUUGGAAAACUGAGGAAUCUUCUGGUUGCAGGUGCAAAGUGACUUUGUUUAUUCUUGUCUCAGUCUCCUUGAUAGCCACUUCACUCUGCUACUACUCAACUUUCUCCUAAAAAUACUUCAUCUAUUUUCAGUCCUUUCUUUCUGUCUACUCAAAAUGGUUCUAUUAACUUUGCAGUCAUGAGCUUGUUCCAGUUACAGUCCCUUUGAAGUUCAGGGUGAUAAACAGAAUAUUCUUCUGUAGAGGAAGAGAAAGGAGUGAAAGUUUAGCCCACUGAGACCUAGAGCUUUGUGAUUUCCUAACCUUGAAACUCUGUAAUCCCUAAAGUUAAAAUCUCCGCAAGUGGCACAACUUCAGAACUAAUAGUAUCACUUUGAUUUUUCUUUUUCCUCCCUUAGAAAGUUUCUCUAGUUCUAUAGUUUAUUUGUUGAAGGUACUAUGACCAAAGAAUCAGCUGCUCUACAGGAAUAGCAUGGUUCCAGUGAAUUAGAGAAAACCUGCUGUAAAGCCAUGGUAGUGUCUAAGUGGUAUGUUAUUAUGAUGUACUAGCAUUUAUUUACAGAAUUAUUUAUUAACGUUUACUUCCUUCCCCUCUGUAAAUGUCCAUGACUAUUGCCCAGAGAAGGCUUACCCCUCUCUAGGGUUGCAGUUGCUUUCUUUGUAAUAAGUAUUUUGCCACACCUGUAAAAAAAAAAACCUCACUUUUAACUCUCUGCCUUGUUUGGGUAAAGGCAGUAACUAAGUUUAUGUUUCAGAACUGCAAAACAAACAGGAUAGUUACCAAUAUGGCCCAUGUAUCAGAUUGAUUUUUGUAGCCUCUCACUGAAUCCAACAUAUCCACAAGCAAGUUAUCUGUCUUUCUACCUGAUAAUCUAAAUUAUCAGGAUAUUUGUUUUCUGCCUAAAUGUUUAUACUAAGCCGAGGGGAGAGAGGUACCUAGACCAUGUCAUCUACAAGCUUCAGUAACUAAAGAAAAAGGAACUUCCCUGAGUGGCUUGAAUGUGUUUGCCCACAGUCUAUAUCUAUGUAUAUAGAAUGUCUGUAUGUAUUUUACUUAUUUAAUAUACAUUGAAUGGUACCUUGCUACAGUAUUUCUGACAUUUAGAGUAGUGUUGAAAUACUCGGCUAGCAUCAGCACCACUAUAGCACUGUCCGUGUCAUAUGAGUCACUAAUAUUAACUCCAGGGACUUCUGGAUAGGCUAAUAGAUCAUUGGAUACGAAGGGCUCUUUUGAAGCUUCAGUAUACCAUGUUUGCAUAGUUUAUCUUUAAAAACAACUUUAAAGGUUCUUUUGUGAGCCAGGAUCUCAGACUGCCGUAGCAUGAUGCUGUCCAUCUUUAGCGCAUGGGCUGAGAACACCUCUUCCCUGAGGCUUCUGAAGGUUGCUGUCUGUCAUGAGUGCAUGAAGGAGGCCAAGAGUUUAUGCUAUGGGAGGAAACAGUCACUGAUUUGCCUAGAUUCUGAGAGUCUGGCCCAUAGCCAACCACAUUUUCCUUUGGGAUAAUUUAUUUCCUGUGGCAUCUAGCCAGAAGAAAUUGAGGAUGUUUCCUUUCACAGCUGCUCCAAGCCUGUUGCCCAAUUCACGGUACAAGGGAGCACCCCUUCCCUUUCCUCUGAAGGUACGCCACCCACCUCCGUCGCCCACCUCAGCGCCCAGGAGCCUUGGGACUUCCUUCCAUAUGAUAAAUCAUUCUUCUUCACGUCAAUACACUUCAUAUUAAUUUCUAGUACAGAAAAUCUUGACAGCUAUCAGAAUGCCUUGGUCAUAGUGUUGUUGCAAAAUUGACCAUACAGGUGGCCCAUGUAUAAAAUCUGAAUUUUAGGGGUUUGUCCCCACCUCGCAUGCUGGCUUUUACAGGGAGGUGUCUGGGAUUCCUCAUUAGCAAUCAAAACUUAAUUACUGGGAUGCAGAGUCCUUACUUUAUCGCCAGCCCGUAGGCAUUUCUGAAGUGCACUUUUUUGAAACAUCAUUUUGCUAACUCUCAGCAGUGUCUAAUUAAACUGAGCAAUACUUUUGUGAAUUUUAAUUAAUCUCAGCAAAACCAUGAUGGGAGAGAGUCCUCUGAUGGAAAUGUAGUCCCUGGAUUAUGUGUAACCUUUUUAUUCCUCUUAGAUGCAGAGGAUAGAAAGCAUUUUUUGGUGCAGUGGUCUUGUGGCAAACACAAGACCCUCUAUGCGUCUCCAACUGUUAUCCUAAUCUAGAAAAUGAGGACUGGCCCCUGGGCAAAAGUGACAUGAGGAAUUUACUCUGGAAGAGGAAAAUCUGGGUGGCUUUCCAAGGCUAAGAUAGGUUUGUAUUUCACCCUGUGGCCAAGCUACAGAACUUCUGAGAUUGUGGAAGAAUUUUUGCAACCAGCAGGGAAAGAGGCCUCUUACUGCCUAAACACAAAGUUACACUGAGCUUUUCUACUGUCCUUUGCCUAUUGCUCCCUCUAUCAUGUAAAGAUCUGGGAAGGAUGAGAGGCAGGGCCUGCUUGUCAUGAGCUGCACUCUUUUCUUUUUAACUAAUCAUUGACAAUUGGAAGAAAAUUGACGUUAAAGAAGUUUCUCCAUUGUCUUACUAACAAAACCUUUUGGGUUUCAUUAAUUGUCCUUGAAAUUGAGUUCCUUUGGCAUUUUUCCUUGCAGUCAUCAGUUAAGCAUGUUGCAUCCUGAAUUCACAGAAGUUUAGCUUUGCAGGUUUGAAUCUCUGUAAUUUAACUCCCGUGGACUUGGUCGAGUUUUCAGCAGGUUGGGAGCCACCUCUCUUCAUUUCAGCAGUGAGUCAUCCCUUGACUUUUCAAAUGACAGAAUUUUUUCCAAUUGUAAAAUUAGCACUGUAAAACAAAGAACCAAAGUGGCAUCCUAAGAGUUGUUAAACCUGAAGUCUAGUUUAUGAGGAAUUGUCCAAGUUGGAGUUUAAAUAGUAUCUGCUUUUGUCUCAAAGCAUCUAAGUUAUUCUGACAGAAAAUGGUAAGUCAGCUUUGCAGGCAGAUGCGCCUCUGGGCCUCCUACCUUGCUCCACAGCUUUCUGGCCAUCUUGUCUCCCAGGCCAUGCCACUGCUCUGCCACAUGUCAGCAAAUUUCUUUCCACCAGUCUUAUAGCAUCUUACAUGAUCAAAUCAUCACAGAAUAACCCCGUGAUAGAUUAUUGAUAGCAAUAGAGAGGGGCUUUGUCACUGAUUUUUCUCUCAGAUUCCUUUUCCAUCUCUCAUCCAUAAAGGAAGGACUGAAAUCCAAAGGCAUUCUCCUUUUGUACCUACAGUAUCCAGAACCCACGUGGGCAGCCUUCUGCUUAUGACAAUAAUUGGCCCAUUGCAUGCAGAGAGAAUGUCUUCAUAGAGAGAAUGUCAUUAAAUACUUGAAUCUGCAUGACAGUUUGACUUGAAUGCAACAGCAGGAAAAUUUUGCAAGUUACAUAAUUGUAUAUACAGUAGGUUUUCUUAAGUCUCUUCGGUUCAUCCUUUGUAAUUUGUGUGUGUAUCUGUAGUAUUGCAGGCUUUUGGAGACUAUUCUUACAGGCAGUAUGUCAGUCAUCAAAGAAAAUGCUGUCACCUGCCAUUGUUGUAUUUGUGGGUAUUUAUAGUUGUAUGUAUGUAAAUGCAUCAGUGUGUAGAUUGCAUAUCAGUGUAUGGUACAUGUACAUCAAAAUUAUUUUUGUCCUUAAUCAGUGUGAUAUGAAAAGCAAGUACAACCUCAUAGGACUGAUUAUAUAAUGAAGUUGUUGAGAGUAUAUAUAGUGGUAUUGUUUUAUUAAACUUAAACUCAAAUAAUAUUUUGAUUAAAAUUUUUAAUAAGACUUUAUGCUAGAAAAUUCUUUGAGCUUUGAAUCACCAGGGCAAAAAUGACUUUCAACUAACCUUGUGAAUCUUUUGCAGUGUACUGUGUGCAAUACCAAGGGCAUAGCUCCCUGUAAUUUGGGAAAUACAGAAAGAAAAGAAAAAAAAAAAAAAAGGCAGCCUGUGCAGUCUUAGUAACUUUAGUAUUAAGAGCACUUAAAGUCAAACUGACAAUUUUGGGCUUAUUACAAAAUGUGAUGCUUUAAAGCACACGUUCUUUAUUGUUGUUGUAAUUAGUCCAUAAAAAAUAUAGCUUUCGGAAGAAUUAAGUACCCACCAUAUCAUUUAUGUAUUUGUGUAUGUUUUACGGGAGAUCAAACCACUCUCGUGGUGCCGCAUCCGUACUCGCUUGACUUGGAAGAAAUAUCACAAGCACUAAAGUAUAUCAGGGCAUCCCAGGAUUGGGUACUGUAUCCUAGGUUUGCAGUUGCAGAAAUUAGCAUCUAGUGUCACAGGUAAAAGAAUUUCAGGACCAGGUUUAAACUUUAUUUUAAAUAUUUUUAUACUUAGGUCUCUUUUUCCUGCCUCUCCCCAAAGAAGAGCCACUGGCCUUAGUUGUUUGAGCUUACUGCUUAUAUUAUAGAGUGUAAAUAGGUAACUAGAGACUAAAAUUUUAUUAACCAGCAUGUUUGGUAUAUUUAAAGCAGUGACUGAGUGUGUUUGAGUGAGUGGCUGAGUGCAGUGUCUUUUGUUUAAACACACUGCCUCGUGUCUUUGUAGCUGAUUCAGAGAGUUUGAAUUGUGGGGUGGGAGACUAACUUCAGCUCCAGGCUGCAGUAAUGUGUUGGUAGUUACACUUGAGGCAUUUUUUUGUUGUUGUUAAUUAACUCUAUAGUCUCAAACUAUUUUUGCAAAUAUAUCAUUUUUCCUAAUUGGUUCUUGACGUGCAGUGGACUGGCUCUGUGAAUGAUUGGCAGGGUCUUAGUUUUGCGAGAGUAUUUCCUUCUAAGAAUUAUUGUGAUCUGCAGAAACAGCCAUUUGAUUCAAAAAUCAUGUAGAAAAGGAGUAGGAGAAGCAAAACGUUUCAUUUUUGGGCCUUAACCAUUUGAAAUGUUUGGACUUUAAACAUAAAGCCAUGGAGUUUAUAAAGCCAAGUAACCAUUUGAUAUGGAUAAUAAUAUCUACUCUAGAGAGAGUAUAUAUAUGCACAUUGAUUUUUAAUGCUGUUAAGAUACUUUUGUAAAACUGUAGGAACAAGAGUAAUUAGACCAAAUUGAAGCUUAGGGGACAGUAAAGUGGUUGCUUUCCAUUUAGGGUAACCAUGCAUGUGGUUAGUCCUCUCCUCCUGAGAUUCAGAACCAGUUGACUGUCCCCUUAGGUGUAUAAGGAGAAAAGUUGACAUGUCUGGGACCUCUGACAUGUGUACACAUGCUUGCACACAUGCACACACAGUGAAUGUUUUAAGUUAUACAAACAUAAGACCUUAAGAUGCAAAGAGCCAGAAUAUUCUAAAGAGGUGAUGAACAGAGGGGGUGGAAACUGCAUCACAGAUGUUUUCCAAGGGCCAGGGUGGAAUCUGAGCUCUAGUGUCUGACUUUGAGAUGCAUUAUAUUUUUAACACAUAAAUGAGGGGAUCCAUAUCACAUUCUUUCUUGUGGACCACCAAAUUGAAGGCUUUCUUGUAAUUCACAAGCAGCAGCUCUCCAGCAUCUCUCCGUAGCCUGGGUGAAGUCCCAGAAGCUGGUGUGCAUCAUUUUCCAAGGUGGCAGAGCUGCUUGCUCUGCAGAUCAUUCCUUUGAGAGAGGAGUACAAGUGAAGAAACAAGGAGGCACUUCCUGUAGGAGCACUGAUGUGCCUUGUCCACACUCCCCUCUGAGCUUUACUGGUAAGAGAGCUCCGACUGAACAUGCUGAGCAGUUGAGCACUUUUCCAUCAGCAACAACAGCGAGGAUGGAAAUGGAAAGGAACCGAACUAAAAUGCAUUUCCCUUUGCAGGGCAGAGAGCUAAGCUCUUAGGAAUAGUGUUAUAGAAAUAAGCACCCUAACUUCAAUUCCUGAAAAUGUUGGUUAAUGGAGAGAAUUUUGGAGUUUCACUUAAUAUUUUCCCAUCGGUCGCCAUAAAUAAGUCUUCAGGCGCUCCUAGAAGAGUCCCAGCCCAAGGCUCGAUUAAGGACCACACUGCAGGUCUGAGGCUCACUGCUCUGAGUCCUGAACACCAGAGCCCUGCAGAGAGUGGUGAUAACACAUCAUCUCUGCAAAGAGGAACCUCUCCCCCGGCCGCCACUUCACUCAGGCUUCUACUGAGCAGCAAGGACAGCCUGGGUUUCAAAUGCCACUUCCCCUGCUUUAGGGAUCCAGGUGUCCUGAUAGCGUGACCCUGCUGAGGCAAGGUAUCAACUCCGAGAGUGACUGAGUCACUGAGCGUGGCACAUGAACAAACGUCAUGACAAAGAUUCUCUGAGUGAAGUUAACACCACGUAUUUUACCUUUGCAAAAAACAAACUGGCACCCUGAGUUCUAACUACGGACGGACGAUAUCUUUGCCUCCACACCCAGAUUCCUGGAAAUGGCUAACGUUUCCUUUCUAGGGGAAGGGUCGAGGAAUACUCAAGUGCUAGCUUAGCAGCUUUGUUCAGUCCAGAUCAGAGCUGUUAGGUAAAGGCCUAACCACCUCCCUGCAGUCUCUUAUAUCUCAAGCUUUAGGAACCCAUUUCUAAAUGUACACUAGCGGAGAAUUUAUAUUGUCAGCCUUGAUUACCAUAGGACAGGCAGAAAGGCGAUAAUUUGUAUCUUUUAAUAUAAAAGAAGCUUUUAACUUUUCCAGCCUAUUAUAAUAACUGAGUUAUAUUCACUGUGGCUCAAACUAAUUGGCAUUGUGGAACAUUUCUUUACCUUCAAAGUUUUCUCCACCAAUCAUUUCAGUUCUAUUGCAGUCCUGGUGCCAUAUGUCCCCUGCAAAUUGUGAAAGUAAUUAGUGACAAAAUAGCAGCCUGCUCCUUUUCAAUGGCGAAACUGUCGGCAUUAGCAGUUUUGGGUAAGCUGGCGGUACUAUAACACGUACUGGAAACCUGUUCCUCAUCACCACCUACCAGAUUCUGGAAAUGCCGUCUUCUAGAAAACGAUGGCGUUUGUGGUGGUCUUCUUUUGAAAGGAACAGUAAUUUGUGUGGAUAUUGUUAAAGUGUUUAAAGAAUAUUUUGACAAUUAAGUUUACAUUUUACAAUUGCUUUAUUUUUUAUUAAAAUAGUUGUAUAUAAAUAUUACCCUAUUUCACUGUUGUUCAAGUAAAUCUAAACCUUGUAGACAAGUGAGUCAUCUGAUAUGUAUAGAAGCUGUGAUAUAUAGAGUACAUUUAUUGUGUAAAUGUUUAUGAAUAUAAUUGUUCCUGUGUUUUUAUAAGUUGGGGAUAUUUUGUUGUUUUACGGCAACAAAAUUUAUUGCAUUUAAAUGGUUUUUAUGUAAUAGAAAUCACGCAAAAUAGUGAAGGAUUUAAAAUAUGUAUAUGAUACAUGUAAAUGUACAAACUUUAGAAAGAAAUAAAUCCAACAAAUUUCAAUCA